CUUGGCAGUCACCAUGAGGGCGCUGGUCCUGCUCGGCUGCCUCCUGGCCUCGCUCCUGUUCUCAGGACAAGCAGAACUGCAAGUCUCCGCGUCGGGUGGCACAGAAGAUGUUGGCAAUUUGUUGGAGAAUCAUUUCUCUGCUGGAGACGCAAGUCUAGAGGAGAAAGAAAGGGCGCUUUAUGCAGACACAGCCCCUCAAGACAAGAAACUGCUCCUUCACUACCCAGAUGGCAGGGAGGCCGAGAGCCCCAAGAAGACCCCCGCGUCUGCCGCCAGCGCGGGCCCCGAUCCUGAAGCCAGCCUCUCCAAUGCCUCAGCCACAGAGUCACCUCCACCUGGGGAAAGGGACGACAGGGACGCUGCGGGGCCUGGGGAGGAAAAGAAUGGCCCACCAGUGGCAAGCGCCCUCCCUCCAGGAGGGGCCAAGGGGCCUGUGGAAGAGGAGUGGCCGGAGCCCAGUUCUGGAGAGGGACAAGGAGAGGAGGAGACUGGGUUUGGGCUCCCCACGGAGGGAACUGCCAGUGGAGAGGCAGGAGGACAGGCUGGGGGCCAUGAACUCCCCGAGGAAGUCCAGGAGGUCCAAGGGGACAGCCUGGUGCAGGGAGCAGUAGCAGGGACAGCAGAGCCAAAGGCAGAGGGGGCCUCUCCUCACUCAGAGGGUGAUGGGGUCGGCCCACUGAACGCAGAGGCCGAGGGCAGCCCUGGGCCUGGCGAGGAGCCUGCAGUGCCAGAGGGAGCCCCUGACGUCGCGGCUGUUGGGGGAGAGUCGGAGCCAGAUAUUGACACACAAGCCAGUGAGGGCACCGAGGACCAGGGGGAGCCCGGCCCAGCUGCAGAGGCCAGUGCAGAGCCUGGGGGCGCCCAAAGCGUUAAGGCAGGGGACACUGAGGAGAACCAGUCCCCAGAGAUGACUGAGGAGGACGCAGAUGAAGCCUCCUCUGAAGAGGAAAGUGGUGAUGGAAGUGGAAGCGAGGAAGAAGGAGGAGUUCCCUCCGAAGAGGAGUCCGAAGAGGACAGCGGCGAUGGGGCUAGCUCAGAAGAAGCAGAGGGCGCCUCCGAGGAGGCCACGGAGCCCCAGGAGGCUGGGGAGCCCCAGGAAGCCAGGGAGCCCCAGGAAGGCGGGGAUCUGCAGGAAGCCGAGGAGUCCCAGGAAGGCGGGGAUCCCCAGGAAGCCGAGGAGCCCCAGGAAGGUGGAGCGCCACAGGAAGGCGGGGAGCCCCAGGAAGGUGGGGAUCCCCAGGAAGCCAGGGAGCCCCAGGAAGCCAGGGAACCCCAGGAAGGUGCAGAGCUUCCGGAAGCCACAGGAACCACAAGUCACAGGGACAGAGGGGCCCAGCCUGGCCCGGAGGAAUUGAAUACAGAGUCCAUGGGCAGUGAGACCCUGGAUAUGAAGGCAGAGGAGCCCGAGGAGGGACAUCAGGGGGAGGGAGAGUCCCAUCAUUGUUGCCCAGGAAGAGACGGAGGAUGCAAAUGAAGAAGCCCCAUUGAGGGACCGCUCCCACAUCGAGAAGACCCUCAUGCUGAAUGAGGACAAGCCAUCCGAUGACUACUCUGCGGUGCUGCAGCGGCUUCGGAAGAUCUACCACUCAUCCAUCAAGCCUCUGGAGCAGUCCUACAAGUACAAUGAGCUCCGGCAGCAUGAGAUCACAGAUGGAGAGAUUACCUCCAAGCCCAUGGUACUGUUCCUGGGACCGUGGAGUGUUGGUAAAUCUACCAUGAUAAACUACCUCCUUGGGCUGGAAAAUACUCGCUAUCAGCUCUAUACAGGCGCUGAACCCACCACCUCUGAGUUCACGGUCCUCAUGCAUGGGCCUAAGCUGAAAACCAUCGAGGGCAUCGUCAUGGCUGCUGACAGCGCCCGUUCCUUCUCACCCCUUGAGAAGUUUGGCCAGAAUUUCCUAGAGAAGCUGAUUGGCAUUGAGGUUCCCCACAAACUUCUGGAGAGGGUCACUUUUGUGGAUACACCAGGCAUCAUCGAGAACCGCAAGCAGCAAGAAAGAGGCUACCCCUUCAACGACGUGUGCCAGUGGUUCAUCGACAGAGCUGACCUCAUCUUUGUCGUCUUUGACCCAACAAAGCUGGAUGUGGGUCUAGAGCUGGAGAUGCUCUUCCGCCAGUUGAAGGGGCGUGAAUCCCAGAUAAGGAUCAUCCUGAACAAGGCUGACAAUCUGGCCACCCAAAUGCUCAUGCGGGUUUACGGGGCCCUCUUCUGGAGCUUGGCCCCUCUCAUCAAUGUCACAGAGCCCCCAAGGGUUUACGUCAGCUCCUUCUGGCCACAAGAGUAUAAGCCGGACACCCAUCAGGAACUGUUCCUCCAAGAAGAGAUCUCCCUCCUAGAAGACCUGAAUCAGGUGAUCGAGAACAGACUGGAGAACAAGAUUGCCUUCAUCCGCCAGCACGCCAUCCGGGUCCGCAUCCACGCCCUCCUGGUUGACCGCUACCUGCAGACUUACAAGGACAAAAUGACCUUCUUCAGUGAUGGAGAACUGGUCUUUAAGGACAUUGUGGAAGAUCCCGAUAAAUUCUACAUCUUCAAGACCAUCCUGGCAAAGACCAAUGUCAGCAAAUUUGACCUUCCCAACCGCGAGGCCUAUAAGGACUUCUUCGGCAUCAAUCCCAUUUCCAGUUUCAAACUGCUCUCCCAGCAGUGCUCCUACAUGGGAGGUUGCUUUCUGGAGAAGAUUGAGCGGGCCAUCACUCAGGAGCUUCCGGGCCUCCUGGGUAGCCUCGGGCUCGGGAAGAAUCCAGGUGCUCUCAACUGUGACAAAACAGGGUGUAGCGAAACACCAAAAAAUCGCUACAGGAAGCACUAGGUGGUGGAGCGGUCCUUGGGUUCCUGUUGGUGAAUCAGCUUGUGUCCUAACUGUCUGAGAGGUCCUGGUUUAUUAACCCUUUGAGCCACACUGGCAGGAAUUAUUACACAGUGGAGAGUUGGGAGUUCAUUGAGGCCAGGGGUCGGGGCAGGUGUGUGGGUCUAGGGAGGAGAGUGGAAACUGUGAAUUCCUGUGUGCUUGUCUUGUUGCUUCAAUGAGGAGGCCUGAUUGAGGCAAGUCAGCCUCCACCUGCUUUUCCUGGGUCCUGUCUUGGAAGGACAGAGAGCAGCUAAAUUCUAGUGUAUCUUAAAUCAGUGAGGGUCAAAUAAGCUAAAAGCAGCUGAAAUUCCUUUGUUCCCUGUGAGCUGGGAAAACAGCGAAGGCCUGAGUCGUAGAGAUUGUCAGGUCCAUUUUGGCUUCUUUCCACACCCACAGUCUCGCGUUUGUUCCCCAGCCCUCGGCUGCCUCUUAACUUUGGGUUGACUUUCAACAGUGAAUAGUCUCUUGGGUCUGAAUAUACCUGGGUUUGUUUUUGUGUUUUUGAGACGGAGUCUCGCUCUGUCGGCCAGGUUGGAGUGCAGUGGUGCAAUCUCAGCUCACUGCAACCUCCCCCUCCUGGGUUCAAGCGAUUCUCCUGCCUCAGCCUCCUGAGUAGCUGAGAUUAUAGGCCUACCACCAUGCCCAGCCAAUUUUUGUAUUUUUAGUAGAAACGGGACUUCACCAUGUUGCCCAGGCUGGCCUCGAACUCCUGACCUCAAGUGAUCCACCCGCCUCGGCCUCCCAAAGUGCUGGGAUUACAGGCAUGAGCUGCCGCACCCGGCCUCCACCUGGGUUUUGAGCCAAUCCCCCGGACUUGCUCCUGGUUUCCUCAAGGGGUGGGGCAGUGGUUUAGGACACUCGACAACUAAGAACAGGAGUUCCCAGGAAGGACAAGGAUCUGCCUCCCCCACUGCCACUUCUCUGAUGUGUUCCUCAAAGCUGGCUCGAGGGCUCGAUCCCUUCAUCGGACCCAGGAGGGGACUGGUUGGUGUAUCCAGGUAAUUUACUCUUGGAAGUGACUGUAGUGAAGGUCGUGGAAGGGCUCAGAGGGUUAAUUGGUUUGCAGUGCGUCUUUGUCUAUUGCAUGUCUUGGAAAACUCAGAUCCCAAAGGCGCUGGGUUUCAGAGAGGACAGUGGAGACCUUGCUCCUUUUCCUUAGGCCGCCAGUCUCUCAAAUUUCAGAGGAGGCUGUUUCCACAACUCCCCUGUGGAAACACUUGGCAGCGGAGUUGCUCCUUUGCAGUUUCCACACCAUGGCUUUUCCUUUCCUUUCUUCUCCAUUCCCUGAUGCAUCAACACUUACUUGGAGCAAUUUCCUAGGAGUCAGAACCAGCACCAGCCACUCGGUGUCGGUGGCCACCAAGGCUUAACAUUGACCUUCCCGCCUGACCUUGAUGCAGAUGUCCACUGAACACACCGCAGGAAAGCCAGGGCCUUCAAUACCAAUAAGUGUGAAUAUGUGUGUAUGUUGUCCAAGAGAGAUUAGGGAGAUCACAUAGACUCUAGGGAGUAGAGAACUUGUAACAGUCUUGCAAGGCUAGCAUGCACGGCUCCACAGCAGGUGGUGGGGAGCAGAGGGGCAGGACCUGCAGGGAAGAAGCAGCCUUUGGAUGGUGAAAUGUGCAUGGUGCACAGUCUGUGCAUGCCCAGGAGACCCAGCCCGGGCUGCCUCGAGGGGCUCCUUUGUACACAGCCAGCCGCUUCUCUUGGGAACAAGCUGUCCUGGGGGCCUUACCCACGAGGCAGGAGUCAGGAUGCACCAGCUCAGCACCAGGAAGUCAUCCUGGACCCAGGACAGUGGAAAGGCAGGCAGAGGGAGAGGCACUCUGAGGUCAGGCAGGGUAAGCCAGUUGGCAGUCAGGUUAGGUCUAUGAGGAGAACCUCGAGUUAGGAAUUCCCGGUUCUCAGAAUUGUUAUCACUCUGGUGCAUGCUGUCACAGGGGCCGUUGCGUUUGGCUUUGUGGAGGGCCUGGACCCUUCCACAAGAACACCCGAGGUUCCAGGGCACUCAGGACAAUGUUUCCAAGGAACGAGUCGACCAGGAAAGAACAGUGAGUUCUGCAAGGGGCAUCCACGGAGCCUGUGAUAGGGGCUGAUGAGAUGGAAUCUGUCCUGGACUUUUCUUCUCAUUAACCACCCUCCGCAAACCCCAGAACCCCUCGCCUCAUCUCUGUACUGUCUGCCCUCUUGGGGGAUGGGCCCUCCCACUUUCCCCUGCCUGCUCCUCCAUGCUGUGAGCUGCUUUGGCAGAUCUGUUUUUCUGUGUAGUCAGGGGAAAAACAAAAAAAGAUGCACAACUGUGUGGGCAUUGUCAUAGCUGUUGGUGUCACCACUGCUUUGGGGGAAAUGGCUGGGAUGAGGCUAAUACAUUCAUGCAAUAUUUAUAUUUUCAGGGGGCUGCGUUAUCAGCAUGCUCUCCCUGCCUUGGGCUUUUCUUUCCGUCAUGUUUUCCUUUUCGUGUUCCUUCUCUGAUUUCUCUUGUCUCUGCUGCUCACAGGCCUGCCCAUCAGUCAGUACAGAUACUCAGUGUCUGGUUUCUGGCCAGCUCCGUGGAGGGGGCUUUAAGCAGAAUUCUGACUCUUUGGGGUGGGGGAUUAGGAACUGGGGGAAACUUAAUGAUCCAGAGAUUCCCCCAAGAGGAGUGUCUGGAAGGAUCUGUGCCUGGACAGUGGCAGAACCUUUCCAGUGUUCUUUUGGUUCUGAUUUCAUCAGUCUCAAUAAAGUUCCGAUCUCUCUUUAA